GGAGUCGACCGCUCGGGCAGCGCCACCGCCACGAGAGCCCGGGACGCGGGAAAGACCGAAAGGAAGAGGAAGAGGCACCGGUGGCCAUGGGGCUGGAGGCGGCGCGCGAGCUGGAGUGCGCGGCGCUGGGCACGCUGCUGCGGGAUCCGCGGGAGGCGGAACGCACGCUGCUGCUGGACUGCCGCCCCUUCCUGGCCUUCUGCCGGCGCCACGUGCGCGCCGCGCGGCCAGUGCCUUGGAACGCGCUGCUGCGGCGCCGCGCGCGCGGCCCUCCUGCCGCCGUUCUCGCCUGCCUGCUGCCCGACCGCGCGCUGCGGACGCGCCUGGUCCGCGGGGAGCUGGCGCGGGCCGUGGUGCUGGACGAGGGCAGUGCCUCGGUGGCGGAGCUCCGGCCCGACAGCCCGGCUCAUGUGCUGCUGGCCGCGCUGCUGCACGAGACCCGCGCGGGGCCCACUGCCGUGUACUUCCUGCGAGGUGAGCAAGCCGGCCGCCCUUGGCCCGCCCCACCCGACUCCAGCCCGGCUUUCCCUGCUGAUCGUGCUCUUCCCCUCCUUGCAGGAGGCUUCGACGGCUUCCAGGGCUGCUGUCCCGAUCUGUGCUCUGAGGCCCCCGCCCCUGCGCUGCCGCCAACAGGGGACAAAACCAGCCGCUCCGACUCCAGGGCUCCUGUCUACGACCAGGGUGGCCCUGUGGAGAUCUUGCCCUACCUGUUCCUGGGCAGCUGCAGUCACUCGUCAGACCUGCAGGGGCUGCAGGCCUGUGGCAUCACAGCCGUCCUCAACGUGUCCGCCAGCUGCCCCAACCACUUUGAGGGCCUUUUCCGCUACAAGAGUAUCCCUGUGGAGGACAACCAGAUGGUGGAGAUCAGUGCCUGGUUCCAGGAGGCCAUAGGCUUCAUUGACUGGGUGAAGAACAGCGGAGGCCGGGUGCUGGUGCACUGCCAGGCGGGUAUCUCGCGCUCUGCCACCAUCUGUCUGGCAUACCUCAUGCAGAGUCGCCGUGUGCGGCUGGACGAGGCCUUUGACUUCGUUAAGCAGCGCCGGGGGGUCAUCUCCCCCAACUUCAGUUUCAUGGGGCAGCUGCUGCAGUUUGAGACCCAGGUGCUGUGUCACUGAGGUGGUGCCCCUCUGCCUGCCUGCCCCACUGUGCUGGCAGGAGCUGACUGUGGACUGGUGGGCUCCCCUCUGGGCCAGCACAGUCCCCUCACCUCUGGCAGGGCUGCUACCUCCUCAGAGUUUCAGAAGCCCCCACAUGGGGGCUCUAGGAAUGCCGGCAUGCUGGUCUUUCCGACCUGGUGCUCUUCUGCUGGGGGACUGAGGCUGGCCCUCAUUCGGGGUCGGGAACCAAGGGUGUGUCUGCUCUUUCCCUCCCCAUCCUCUGGCAGAAAUCAGCUAGACGCUAUACCGUGGACUCUCCCUGGUCCACCACCAUGUUGAAGCCCUUGGCAGCCUGAGAGCUCCAAGGAACAAGCUGUGACAACCAGGAGCCCUGUCUGUGGGUUCGUCUGCCCAGGGCCUGGAGCCCAAGCCCUGUGUUCCUGGGGAAGCUGGGGACUUGGGAAGUGAUGGGUGUGUCAUGUUGCGUGUGUCUGUCUGUGAGCCUUUCACACCUGUGCUGGCGCUGGAAAAUUAUUUGUGCUCAGCUGACAUUUAACACUCCCUCCCCCGCUUCCUCCUAGCCCUGUGGGCAGGGGUUGGAAACUUAGCACUUUAUAUUUAUACAGAACAUUCAGGAUAUGUCAAUAAAAUAUUGUUAUAUUUAAAAAACAA